GUUUCCGGUUCGCCUCCGGAGCCAUGGCGGCGGCACUGAAGUGUCUACUGACAUUAGGAAGAUGGUGCCCCGGCCUUGGAGUGGCUCCCCAGGCCCGGGCGCUCGCCGCCUUAGUACCCGGAGUGACCCAGGUAGAUAACAAGUCCGGUUUCCUGCAGAAGAGGCCUCAUCGCCAGCACCCUGGCAUCCUAAAGCUGCCGCACGUGCGGCUGCCACAGGCACUGGCUAACGGUGCCCAGUUAUUGCUACUUGGGAGCGCUGGGCCCACUAUGGAGAAUCAGGUGCAAACACUGACCAGUUAUCUCUGGAGCAGACAUUUGCCUGUAGAGCCAGAGGAGUUGCAAAGACGGGCUAGGCAUCUUGAGAAAAAAUUCCUGGAAAACCCAGACUUAUCUCAGACAGAGGAGAAACUUCGUGGAGCAGUGCUACACGCACUACGUAAAACUACCUACCAUUGGCAAGAACUGAGCUACACUGAGGGACUGAGCCUGGUGUAUAUGGCAGCAAGACUGGAUGGUGGCUUUGCAGCAGUCUCCAGAGCAUUCCAUGAGAUCCGGGCUCGAAAUCCAGCAUUUCAGCCACAAACUUUGAUGGACUUUGGCUCAGGUACUGGUUCUGUCACCUGGGCUGCUCACAGUAUUUGGGGCCAGAGCCUACGUGAAUAUAUGUGUGUGGACAGAUCAGCUGCCAUGUUGGUUUUGGCAGAAAAACUACUGAAAGGUGGUUCAGAAUCUGGGGAGCCUUAUAUUCCAGGUGUCUUUUUCAGACAGUUUCUACCUGUAUCACCCAAGGUGCAGUUUGAUGUAGUAGUGUCAGCUUUUUCCUUAAGUGAACUGCCCAGCAAGGCUGACCGCACUGAGGUAGUUCAAACCUUAUGGCGUAAGACAGGUCAUUUCCUGGUACUGGUGGAGAAUGGAACAAAAGCUGGGCACAGCCUUCUCAUGGAUGCCAGGGAUCUGGUCCUUAAGGGAAAAGAGAAGUCACCUUUGGACCCUCGACCUGGUUUUGUCUUUGCCCCGUGUCCCCAUGAACUCCCUUGUCCCCAGUUGACCAACCUGGCCUGUAGCUUCUCACAGGCGUACCAUCCCAUCCCCUUCAGCUGGAACAAGAAACCAAAGGAAGAAAAGUUCUCUAUGGUGAUCCUUGCUCGGGGGUCUCCAGAGGAGGCUCAUCGCUGGCCCCGUAUCACUCAGCCUGUCCUUAAACGGCCUCGCCAUGUGCAUUGUCACUUGUGCUGUCCAGAUGGGCACAUGCAGCAUGCUGUGCUCACAGCCCGCCGGCACGGCAGGUAUGGGGGGUGUGACCAAAAUCAGUGGGAUGUGGCAGGAAGCUGCAGCCCACGCCAGCAUCUGUUUCCACAGGGAUUUGUAUCGUUGUGCCCGUGUCAGCUCCUGGGGAGAUCUUUUACCUGUGCUUACUCCGUCUGCGUUUCCUCCAUCUACGGCUCAGGAUCCCUCUGAGAGUUGAUGAGGAUGUGUAACAAGUAUUUUCUUCUAUCGUGCCUGCCAGGGCUGAAGCUGCCUGGUAUCCAGGAGGGGAAUGCUGGUAUCCCCAUAUGUCUGUGUUUGUUUGAGAUUUUUAAUAAUAAAUAAUAAAUUUUUGAAGAAUGGAA